GAGCACACCAGCCAGGAAGGGGGACCUGGCAGGCUGGGGACAGCCUCCUCUCCGGGACUGAGCUGUAAGGAACAGACCUCUCUGGCUAUCGUUGGGGAGUGAGGCAAAGUUACCGUGAGUCUUAUGUUUUGUCUGCUAAGGUUUCGGAGGAUUAAUAAUUCAGGCCAUGCUUUGAAACAGAAAACCCCCAGUUGGUUGUCCCUGCCGUCUCGGAAGGGUUAGCACACAGCCAGGUCUGUUUUUGAUGUAUGUAAUUGAAGAUUUAUAAAGAAAAGCUUCUCCUCUGCCUCAUCCGCAGUCAUUUUUUUUCCAAUGCCAGUUCCCAGCAGGCAUAUAAAUAUUGGUCGUUCUCAGAGCUGGGAUGCUGCUGGGUGGUACGAGGGCCCCUGGGAGAACGCCGAGUCCCUGCGGCCUCUGGGGAGGAGAAGCUCCCUGACGUAUGGCACAGCAGAGGGGACUUGGUUUGAGCCAAACCACCGACCACAGGACGCUGCCCUGCCCGUGGCCGCCGAGCCCUACCUGUACCGGGAGGCCGUUUAUAACUCAGUGGCUGCAAGAAAGGGGUCUACUCCUGACUUCACCUUCUACGACAGCAGACAGGCAGUGAUGUCUGGUCGCAGCCCCCUGCUGCCACGGGAGUACUACAGUGAUCCGUCUGGAGCUGCUAGGGUACCCAAAGAGCCUCCCCUCUAUCGGGACCCAGGAGUCAGCCGGCCGGUCCCCAGCUACGGAGUGCUUGGCAGCAGAACGUCAUGGGAUCCAAUGCAAGGCCGGUCACCUGCCCUGCAGGACGCCGGUCACCUGUACCGGGAUCCUGGAGGUAAAAUGAUCCCUCAGGGGCGGCAGACACAGAGCAGGGCUGCAUCUCCCGGGCGGUAUGGACGGGAGCAGCCCGACACCAGGUAUGGGGCGGAGGUGCCUGCCUACCCCCUCAGCCAGGUCUUCAGCGACAUCAGCGAAAGACCCAUUGACCCUGCCCCUGCCAGACAGGUGGCCCCGACGUGCCUGGUUGUGGACCCCAGUUCAGCUGCUGCCCCCGAAGGCAGCACAGGGGUGGCCCCAGGGGCCCUGAAUCGUGGCUACGGGCCUGCCCGGGAAAGCAUCCCAUCCAAGAUGGCUUACGAGACUUACGAAGCUGACCUGUCCACCUUCCAGGGUCCUGGUGGCAAGAGGACCGUGCUCCCUGAGUUCCUGGCCUUUCUGCGGGCGGAGGGGCUGGCAGAGGCCACGCUGGGAGCCCUACUGCAGCAGGGCUUUGACUCCCCGGCCGUCCUGGCUACCCUGGAGGACGCGGAUAUCAAGUCUGUCGCACCCAACCUGGGCCAGGCCCGUGUUCUGAGCCGCCUGGCCAAUAGCUGCAGGACCGAAAUGCAGCUGCGGAGGCAGGACCGGGGGGGCCCGCUGCCCCGGGCGCGGUCCAGCAGCUUCAGCCACCGAAGCGAACUGCUCCAUGGUGACUUGGCUUCUCUGGGCGCUGCGGCUCCUCUGCAGACAGCAUCCCCCCGAGCUGGAGACCCGGCUCGCCGUCCCUCCAGCGCACCAUCUCAGCACCUCCUGGAGACGGCAGCCACCUAUUCUGCCCCUGGCGUGGGCACCCAUGCCCCACACUUCCCCUCCAACUCCGGGUACAGCUCUCCCACCCCUUGCGCCCUGACAGCGCGUCUGAGCCCCACGUACCCCCUGCAGGCAGGGGUGGCCUUGACUAACCCGGGCCCCUCAAACCCCCUUCACCCAGGCCCCAGAACAGCCUACUCCACGGCAUACACGGUGCCCAUGGAGCUGCUAAAGAGGGAGCGCAACGUGGCCGCCUCUCCGCUGCCCAGCCCUCACGGCAGCCCCCAGGUCUUGCGGAAGCCAGGUGCACCCCUGGGGCCAUCCACCCUGCCGCCGGCCAGCCAGAGCCUCCACACGCCUCACUCACCGUACCAGAAGGUGGCCCGGCGCACAGGGGCACCCAUCAUCGUGUCCACCAUGCUUGCACCAGAACCAAGUAUCCGCCCCCAGAUCAUGAACGGCCCCCUGCACCCCCGCCCCCUGGUGGCGCUGCUGGACGGCCGCGACUGCACUGUGGAGAUGCCCAUCCUGAAGGACCUGGCCACUGUGGCCUUCUGUGACGCGCAGUCGACGCAGGAAAUCCACGAGAAGGUUCUAAACGAAGCCGUGGGCGCCAUGAUGUACCACACCAUCACCCUCACCAGGGAGGACCUGGAGAAGUUCAAGGCCCUGAGAGUGAUCGUGCGGAUAGGCAGUGGCUAUGACAACGUGGACAUCAAGGCUGCCGGCGAGCUCGGAAUUGCCGUGUGCAACAUCCCGUCUGCAGCCGUGGAAGAGACAGCGGACUCUACCAUCUGCCACAUCCUCAACCUGUACCGGAGGAACACGUGGCUGUACCAGGCACUGCGGGAAGGCACGCGGGUUCAGAGCGUGGAGCAGAUCCGCGAGGUGGCCUCGGGAGCGGCCCGCAUCCGUGGGGAGACGCUGGGCCUCAUUGGCUUUGGUCGCACGGGGCAGGCGGUUGCAGUUCGAGCCAAGGCCUUUGGAUUCAGCGUCAUAUUUUAUGACCCCUACUUGCAGGAUGGGAUCGAGCGGUCCCUGGGCGUGCAGAGGGUCUACACCCUGCAGGAUUUGCUGUAUCAGAGCGACUGCGUCUCCUUGCACUGCAAUCUCAACGAACAUAACCACCACCUCAUCAAUGACUUUACCAUAAAGCAGAUGAGGCAGGGAGCAUUCCUUGUGAACGCAGCCCGUGGCGGCCUGGUGGACGAGAAAGCCUUAGCACAAGCCCUCAAGGAGGGCAGGAUACGAGGGGCAGCCCUCGACGUGCAUGAGUCAGAGCCCUUCAGCUUUGCUCAGGGUCCGUUGAAAGAUGCCCCGAAUCUCAUCUGCACUCCUCACACUGCCUGGUACAGUGAGCAGGCGUCACUGGAGAUGAGGGAGGCAGCUGCCACCGAGAUCCGCCGAGCCAUCACAGGUCGCAUCCCAGAAAGCUUAAGAAAUUGUGUGAACAAGGAAUUCUUUGUCACAUCAGCGCCUUGGUCAGUAAUAGACCAGCAAGCAAUUCAUCCUGAGCUCAAUGGUGCCACAUACAGAUAUCCGCCAGGCAUCGUGGGUGUGGCUCCAGGAGGACUUCCUGCAGCCAUGGAAGGGAUCAUCCCUGGAGGCAUCCCAGUGACUCACAACCUCCCGACAGUGGCACAUCCUUCCCAAGCGCCCUCUCCCAACCAGCCCACAAAACACGGGGACAAUCGAGAGCACCCCAACGAGCAAUAGCAGAGAAUGCCAGAAGGUAAUCACUCAGAUACACUUGGGACCAAGAGACAGUGAAAAAUAGAUGAACUAAGAGAAAAAGAAUCGGAUGGUCUUUGUAACUGAUUCUGGACAUAUGCAUCAUUGAUGUUGCAGUGUUGAAACUACAAGAGCUAGAAAACUGAAGAUGUCGUCUGCUUACGGAAGCGCUGAAAGACUAGGAUGUGAUUUAUUAACGACCAACUUCUGUUAUUGUGUGUUAAGUUUUUCAUCUGUGCAUCAAAUCACAAAAAGAAUAAAUAGAGCUUUUUCCUUUAUCAGUCCCUUGGGCACAGCAGGUCCUGAACACCCUGCUCUACAAUGUUGCAUCAAGAGUUCAAACAACAAAAUAAAAAAUAUUAAGAGGAAAUCCCCAUCCUGUGACUUGAGUCCCUUAAGUCUACAGGGGCUGGUGACCUCUUUUUGCUAAUAGGAAAAUCACAUUACUACAAAAUGGGGAGAAAACUGUUUGCCUGUGGUAGACACCUGCACGCAUAGGAUUGAAGACAGUACAGGCUGCUGUACAGAGAAGCGCCUCUCACAUCUGAACUGCAUACUGAGCGGGCAAGUCGGUUGUAAGUUCAGUAAAACCCUCUGAUGAUGCAAAAAAAAAAAAAAAAGUAUUAAGUUUCACAAGCUGUUUGUACUCAAAUAUAUUUUCUCAGUUUCAGAUCCUCUGCUAUUUUAUUGAGUGGAAAGUCUUGAGCUAAAAGGGUUCAAGAAGAAUAAUGUUGCAUUUCCUUAUGUCUCAGGAAACACUUUUUAUGGUAACUUGUCAGAUUGUCUAUGAACAAACCCACUUUUUUAGACAUUGAUAAAGUCUUCUUUUCUUCACGUGAUAUUUUAUACAAGAACACUUCAGAUGUAUUAGAUGUGACUGAUUUUAACAAAUCCUAUUAGAUUUGUAUCAACUAGUUACAUGUUCUAUUCAUAGUCUUUUGUGAAUCAUUGCCUUUUUGUUUAAAAAGAUGGCCUAUUUUGAGCCUUUGUAUAGGUACAUUCCUGUUUUUGUGACAAAAGAAAAACUUUAAAAUUGUCCCAAACAGAAAAAUAAUGGCUAUCAGAAGUAUGUUUUGUUUUAGUGUGAGUUACCGUUACUGUAUUUGUUUAUUGUAAAGGUGGACAUUUAGCGUUCAGUGCAGUUUUCAAUAAAAAGUAAUUAAAAUUUGUUAAGUUCUGAAAUUCAAGUACAUCUCACUAAUGUAAAUGUUCUCUACUUGAGAUGUUUAAGGCAAUUGCAUUGUCAAUUAGCCAAUUUCCAGCUCUUGUUACUACAGGGUUCCAUAACCAGACUCAAGACCGCUGACAAUUAAUUACCUGUGAUAACAAAAAGUUUAAUUGAAAAAUCAAAACCUCACACAAGUCCAUCAUUAUCACGUCAUGCCAUCCUUAAGAUGCAAUGGUGGGUUAGUGCUAAAUCAAUUCAAAAAAAAACAAAGUUGCUCAACUUUUAGAGUUCUGACUUUAAUCUACCCCAAAGCAAAAUGACCUGGACCUGGUUCAAGGGAGGGAAGUGAACCUUGAAACUGUUUUGCCAAUAACCUAACAAACAAAAUGAUAUUUACAAAGAAGUGUUGCAAAUAGUCCCAUGAGUUAAGAGCUUGAUUUAAUGGAUCUUCUUUUUAAAUAGAAUUAAACCUUUAUACUAAAAGUAUUUGCAAGUGUCAAUUAAGUCCAACAAUUCCAGGUAUGAAACUCCCUCUGAGCUCUUCCUUAUACUUCCCUUCCCAAUUAAAACAAAACAAGAAAAUCAUGGUGUCUUAAAGCCUUUGGCUUGCCUGGCCUUGUCUGCUCACUCAUUUUAAGGUGGUGGCCCCAUCCCAACUCUACCAUAAAAGUGUCUAUUAACACAAGCUCACAUGGAGAGAGACGGCGCUCAUAGUUACUGACCUAUUACCCCAGGGAACAAAAAGGUAGUUUAACGUCUUCGUAACCACUCAUCAAAGAGGCAAUGAAAUAUGCGUGAAAAGGAGGCCAAGCGCACACAGAAUAUCUUACCUUCACGAAUAUGUGAAGAAGUCUGGGACACGAUGAACCUAAGAGUCAAAAACAUAAAAAGGCAGGUCUGAAUCCAUGGUCCACCUGGGUUUUAAUUAUUAGAUCUUGGUCGCCCAAACAAAAAUUUAUAUAUAUAUAUAUAAAUUUGACCCCAAGGAAGAACAAGUCAAAACAAAAUGCCACGCUCUGUUUGCUCUAGAAAAAGAACCAUCAAGUCCACAGAGUGCAGGUAUGACUUACUCUCCAGAGUCAGUCAUUAAUGUCUGUCACCUAGCCACGUAUAAUCAUCUUUGAAAAAGGACUAUAUUCUAUCUUGGGACAAUAAUUAUGGCUGUUUUAAUAGUUCAAGAGCAUAAUAUAGCAUUGAUUUACCAAAAUUUUUGGCCUUUAACAGCCAGUCUAUGAAAACCAUUUAGAGCCCCAUUCCUGUCUGUAGCCUAGGAAAUGGAACCAUCUUUAAUUCUUUCCCACAGGGAAGAAUGCUGCACCUAUCACACUAUGUGGUCAGGGUCACUGAUUGAUAAUAAAUAAAUAAAUAAUAGAGCGCUCAGGGGAAACAACACUCACCAGACCACAACACACAGUAGAAGCUAAGUGCUGAGCGUGUACUCUGGACAACGCUGGCUGCAAUGCAGACUGCAAUGGCUACAUGCUUUUCCCUCUAACAAUUCUCUUUGGCUUUUUCAAUUGGGAGGGCAGAUUUUGCUUAACAGGCAACUAGAACAGGAUCUCUGCCCACUAAAAAAUUAUCCCUAUACAUAGAGAAAUUACUACAGAUGCUAAGUAGUCAGAAUGCUAACAUUUUCUACAAACUUGAUUACUUAUUGGCCAAAAUGAAAGCAAACAGCCAAUUUUUAACAACACAUUCACCACUUGAAACAAACAGCAGCAUUUACAUUAUAUCAAAGAUUCAUUUCUACAGAAUCGUACUAAAAAAUCAUUUUUCCUGCAAGAUUUAGCAUGCAGCAAAAAAUGAUCUUUUCAUCCUGGGAACACCUUUUUACUGAGUUUUCGGGGGGAAAGAACUAAAGACAUGACAGUUUUGUGGGUAUUUUUCUAUUUUUAGUAUUCUGGCAGCAAAUUUGAGGUUGUACACAUUUCAUUAUCAACUAAACAAAACAAGAAGCAAGCAAAUACUUUAAGGUUUUCACAGCCUUUUUCAUCACAGGGAAGGAAAAAACUGUGUGUGUGUGUGUGUGUGUGUGUGUGUGUGCGCGCGCGCGCGUGCGUGUGUCGUCUUUCCAAAUUCCUGGCCACAUCAAUAGUCUAGAAAGUGCUUAUCAGGACACCAAAUAUUUCUGUGUUCCUGAGAUAGGUCUGAAAUUUUUACCCAGUAUUGAAUGUAUACCUGAAGUGGUCAAAUAAUACUUCUUAUAAAAAAGUUUUUCUACCUAAGAUUAUAGUUUUAACUUUAAAUUAAAGAAUGGCCACAAUUAACCAACAUGCAAAAAUUCUCAGACUAAACACUGAGAAAUUCUUCAUACAAUGCAUUUGCCACCUUAUUGCAUUUUUAAAAUCUUUAUUCUGUAGUGAAUUGGUAUUCCCAAUCUGCCUAAGCAAAGGCAUGCCCUUCUAACAAGAUUUGCUUAGAGCAGAGGUGAUAGAAGGAAGAAUCCGAAGACCCUCUGGCAUGGCAAUCUGGGAGCAGCACAUUGUUGAUGGAGUCCAAGUGAGCACAUUUCACACAAUUCAUUUAGUGACAAGUGGGCUUGCUCCCUUUUCAUCCAGGAAAAAAACUACUCACAGACCACUGCCCAGAAUCUGGAAUAAGAACCCUCAUUUUAAGGUAUUCUUCCCAACAAAUAAAUAUCUAAAUAUUGAAAGGGGGCAUAUCAGAAAACUUAAAGACACAAUAACCAAAACCAAAACCCUCUUCAAAACAAGUAAGCAAUGUCUGUAUUUAGUUCACUCUAAAACAUUCUUAGCUUUUCUUGCAGUUUGUUCCUAAAAGAUUUGAUUGGGCACAAGAGGAACGAAAUUAUUAAUAAAAUAAAAGCUUAUUUUUGUUUUGCUGUGGAUAAUCGGUACAAAACGUUUCCAGAUCUGAGACUUAGAUGGAUCUUUUAAGGUGAAAGUAGAAUGCCAGGUUCUACUGAAAUAAUAUCUGAAAGGAACAAAGAGCCAUUUGCCAUGUGCUUUUUCUAAGUGCCCAUGCUGGAAAAAAUUUUCUCAAUAAUAUGAAGAUGCUGGUACAACUUUUCCUAUUAAACAAUGUCUUACACAACCACAUGCGUUACAUUUAUAGACAGAUUUACAAUUUGGAAGGAAAAAAAGUUCUGUCUUAAUAAAAUUAGUUUUUUUUACAAACUGUAGUCCAACUAAAGUUCUCUGUCUCCUCACGCAGCAGAGGCAUUAUCUCCAUAAGGUGUGUGUGGUCCAGGAAAACACUUCCCCGAGCAGAUCCUGCCAGAUUUGGUUCAUUCCAUGAUGUCGACUCUGCUUGGAGCACCACACUAACUUUAGGGUCAUUACAGAUCUGAUGCCUUGGUCUUCUGCUGUUUGAUUUUUUUUUUCAUUCAUCUUCAUCAUCCUCAUCUUCCUCUCCAUCAGACAGGGAUGUACACGGCCGGAUCUGUCGGUAGCGGUCAAGCCAUUUUUCUACCAUCUGAGUGACCAGGGGGUGAUUUCGCCGCCGAGAACUCUUCUGCAUGGCAACCAGAACUCCCCCCUCCGUCACACAGCAGUCCAGCCACUCCCUGAGCAGUUUUUCUUGCUGUUCCUCAUUACCUAGCUUUUGGAGGAAUAUGAAGACAAAGGGAAAAUCAUACAACAGAUCAGAGACUUGGUAGGAAUGUGACAUGGAAACCUACAGCUGGUAUGCUAACUCAUGAAAAGGCCAAAGCAAUCAACUUUUCACAUGGUUUUGACCUCUUGGAAGUUUUGUGAUUAAAGUCCAGUUUGCUCUGGUUAAAUUUAAAAAGACAUAAAUGGGAAAUUUCUCAGAAAAAAACUAAAGAGGAGCACACUAGAGGGUAAUUUGUUAGAUAAAAUAAAAAACAAAUGUCCUAAUAAACUGAUCCUGGCAAGCCACAGCUUCAAACACAUGACAAGGUAAGUUUACUUAGUCAAUUAUGUACAAGCUGAAAUUAUACAAGUUACGGUCUAUGAACUUUUUUUCUUCAUGUUGUGAUUAUAAACGUUUUAUAAUUACUAGUAUAUUAAAUAAAAGACCAAUACUUUUAUAAGAA